GAGUGUUCUGAGGGAAGCAAGGAGGCGGCGGCGGCCGCAGCGAGUGGCGAGUAGUGGAAACGUUGCUUCUGAGGGGAGCCCAAGAUGACCGGUUCUAACGAGUUCAAGCUGAACCAGCCACCCGAGGAUGGCAUCUCCUCCGUGAAGUUCAGCCCCAACACCUCCCAGUUCCUGCUUGUCUCCUCCUGGGACACGUCCGUGCGUCUCUACGAUGUGCCGGCCAACUCCAUGCGGCUCAAGUACCAGCACACCGGCGCCGUCCUGGACUGCGCCUUCUACGAUCCAACGCAUGCCUGGAGUGGAGGACUAGAUCAUCAAUUGAAAAUGCAUGAUUUGAACACUGAUCAAGAAAAUCUUGUUGGGACCCAUGAUGCCCCUAUCAGAUGUGUUGAAUACUGUCCAGAAGUGAAUGUGAUGGUCACUGGAAGUUGGGAUCAGACAGUUAAACUGUGGGAUCCCAGAACUCCUUGUAAUGCUGGGACCUUCUCUCAGCCUGAAAAGGUAUAUACCCUCUCAGUGUCUGGAGACCGGCUGAUUGUGGGAACAGCAGGCCGCAGAGUGUUGGUGUGGGACUUACGGAACAUGGGUUACGUGCAGCAGCGCAGGGAGUCCAGCCUGAAAUACCAGACUCGCUGCAUACGAGCGUUUCCAAACAAGCAGGGUUAUGUAUUAAGCUCUAUUGAAGGCCGAGUGGCAGUUGAGUAUUUGGACCCAAGCCCUGAGGUACAGAAGAAGAAGUAUGCCUUCAAAUGUCACAGACUAAAAGAAAAUAAUAUUGAGCAGAUUUACCCAGUCAAUGCCAUUUCUUUUCACAAUAUCCACAAUACAUUUGCCACAGGUGGUUCUGAUGGCUUUGUAAAUAUUUGGGAUCCAUUUAACAAAAAGCGACUGUGCCAAUUCCAUCGGUACCCCACGAGCAUCGCAUCACUUGCCUUCAGUAAUGAUGGGACUACGCUUGCAAUAGCGUCAUCAUAUAUGUAUGAAAUGGAUGACACAGAACAUCCUGAAGAUGGUAUCUUCAUUCGCCAAGUGACAGAUGCAGAAACAAAACCCAAGUCACCAUGUACUUGACAAGAUUUCAUUUACUUAAGUGCCAUGUUGAUGAUAAUAAAACAAUUCGUACUCCCCAAUGGUGGAUUUAUUACUAUUAAAGAAACCAGGGAAAAUAUUAAUUUUAAUAUUAUAACAACCUGAAAAUAAUGGAAAAGAGGUUUUUGAAUUUUUUUUUUUAAAUAAACACCUUCUUAAGUGCAUGAGAUGGUUUGAUGGUUUGCUGCAUUAAAGGUAUUUGGGCAAACAAAAUUGGAGGGCAAGUGACUGCAGUUUUGAGAAUCAGUUUUGACCUUGAUGAUUUUUUGUUUCCACUGUGGAAAUAAAUGUUUGUAAAUAAGUGUAAUAAAAAUCCCUUUGCAUUCUUUCUGGACCUUAAAUGGUAGAGGAAAAGGCUCGUGAGCCAUUUGUUUCUUUUGCUGGUUAUAGUUGCUAAUUCUAAAGCUGCUUCAGACUGCUUCAUGAGGAGGUUAAUCUACAAUUAAACAAUAUUUCCUCUUGGCCGUCCAUUAUUUUCUGAAGCAGAUGGUUCAUCAUUUCCUGGGCUGUUAAACAAAGCGAGGUUAAGGUUAGACUCUUGGGAAUCAGCUAGUUUUCAAUCUUAUUAGGGUGCAGAAGGAAAACUAAUAAGAAAACCUCCUAAUAUCAUUUUGUGACUGUAAACAAUUAUUUAUUAGCAAACAAUUGAUCCCAGAAGGGCAAAUUGUUUGAGUCAGUAAUGAGCUGAGAAAAGACAGAGCAUAUCUGUGUAUUUGGAAAAAUAAUUGUAACGUAAUUGCAGUGCAUUUAGACAGGCAUCUAUUUGGACCUGUUUCUAUCUCUAAAUGAAUUUUUGGAAACAUUAAUGAGGUUUACAUAUUUCUCUGACAUUUAUAUAGUUCUUAUGUCCAUUUCAGUUGACCAGCCGCUGGUGAUUAAAGUUAAAAAGAAAAAAAUUAUAGUGAGAAUGAGAUUCAUUUCAAUGUAAUGCACUAAAGCAGAACACGAACUUAGCUUGGCCUAUUCUAGGUAGUUCCAAAUAGUAUUUUUGUUGUCAAACUUUAAAAUUUAUAUUAAUUUGCAAAUGUAUGUCUCUGAGUAGGACUUGGACCUUUCCUGAGAUUUAUUUUAUCCGUGAUGUAUUUUUUUUAAUUCUUUUGAUACAGAGAAGGGUCUUUUUUUUUUUAAGUAUUUCAGUGAAAACUUGGUGUAAGUCUGAACCCAUCUUUUGAAAUGUAUUUUCUUCAUUGCAGGUCCACCUAAUCAUCCUGUGAAAGUGGUUUCUCUAUGGAAAGCUUUGUUUGCUUCCUACAAAUACAUGCUUAUUCCUUAAGGGAUGUGUUAGAGUUACUGUGGAUUUCUCUGUUUUCUGUCUUACAAGAAACUUGUCUAUGUACCUUAAUACUUUGUUUAGGAUGAGGAGUCUUUGUGUCCCUGUACAGUAGUCUGACGUAUUUCCCCUUCUGUCCCCUAGUAAGCCCAGUUGCUGUAUCUGAACAGUUUGAGCUCUUUUUGUAAUAUACUCUAAACCUGUUAUUUCUGUGCUAAUAAACGAGAUGCAGAACCCUUGAAUGUUGGAUGUUUUUGAAUGUUGGUAAUUAAUAUAAUUUACUUAAAAAGGCUUGUGUAAGGCAAAACUCGUCAUCACAGGCAUGUUGGGGGAUGACAUUUUACCUUUAAGUCCACUCUCCCUCGUUUAAUUGUCUCCUCUGAUGUGUGUUGGGGAUUCAGUCCUGCAUAAAGUGAUUUGUUGGAGUUCAGCCAUUUCCCUCAUGCCCCCUUGUGCCCUCUCGGUGGAUCAGCAGGGCCUUUGAGCCAAGUGUGCAGCUUCACUCAGGAUGGGCAGAGACUAUGUGGCAGCCUCUGGGGACCUUUUGGCUCAGUGCUUUACUAGUGCCAGCGCAGUAGUGCUUAGGUAGCUUGUGCAUCCCCGUGUUGAUGUAGUCAUAGUCCACACAGAGCCAAAUAACAGACCCUUCUGUACUUAGCCAUCAAAUACUAAAUCACAGUGAAGCCCUUGGGAAGGUAAAUAAUGUAAUAGCCAGGGACUGAUGGUAUUAGUUCUUUAGUGUGAUUAUGUGCUUCUAAAAGUCCCUAACCACUUGGUUGAGGACAGACCAUAAGUUUAAAACAUUGUAUAAGUGAAAGAAUUAAUAUAGUAUUGUUAUAGGUAACCAAAUUAUAGUAAUGUGGACUUGUUUUUGAGGUGGUGAGGGAGGGCUUAUUUUGUGGUUCCAUCUGGAUGUCCUCUUGUCUCUGGAAAUCAAGUGUGCCUCCCUGCCAUCUCUACAUACCCCUUAACCAGCUCUCCACAAUUUACUUGUUUAUGGUUAUAGCUACCUUUUCCCCAAGUUACCCAGGUGUAGUUACCUUGGCCUUCUCAUUGGUUUCCCUCACCCACAUUCUUUAAGUGUCUCUUCUGUUUAUCUUUUCUUCCUACUGCUACCAUCCCAGGGCCUUUUGGGUGAAUGUGGCAGCCUCCAAUUUCUGCCUUAAGUCCUCCAUCUAAUAGAGUAGUGACUUUUGAACCUUGUAGUUGUGACCCAAGUAAGAAAUACAUUUUGAACUACAGUUCAGAACACAGAGGUCAGUAUAUUAUACAUGACAGAAGGAUCCUGAAAUAUGACUUGCCCUUCUUGCAUGCGAUGUAUCUGGUGCAUGUGUGCAUUUUUUUCUUUGCUUUUUAAGAAAUCCUGGCUAUGUCACCUUGAAUUGAUUUUACAACAAAUGCCUGUCACCUGUAAUUUGCAAAAACUGCUUGAUCAGAUUCUAAAAAAUUUCUAAAAGAUUUUUAAAAAAUGUAUUCUGAUGUCAUACUUGGAAUCCUCCACUGCUUCCUGUUGCUCAUAGUCACCCUUCAGUGAUUUCAUAAGGAGGUGUGCUGCUUCCCAAGCUUCUAGAUCAUCAGGAAGGGGCCGCGGACUGUAAGGUGCUCUCAGAAGAUGGGACUAACCUUUGUUGGGAAUAUAAAUAAGUGGAUGGGAUGGGAAGUGACAGCAAUAUCUGGUUCUGAGUUCUGUUGUGUAAAAACUUAAAGGUAUAUUAGCAGGUUAGCCUUUGUUCUGUGGGAGAUCCAGGCCUUGUUAGAAGGACCAAGGCCAGAAUGCCCAGUUUAGCCUUAGCAUUCAAACCCUUCAUUGUUUUUCCUCCAUUAUCUGUUAAACUCCUGCUUUGCCAAAGGUAUCUUCUAUACCCUAAUAACACUAGCUUCCUUCCCUCAGUGGGGACUCAACGCACAUUAGCCUACUGAGAGCUUAGAUCACUACAACGAAUCCUUGUAAAUUUGUUUAACUCAGUUUUCCCCAAAUUCAUUUAAGCCGGUUCUACUUUUUCUGGUCUUGUUCCCACAAUCAUUUUACCUUUUACCACUCCCCCAGAAAACACUGGGGUUCUUCUCUUACGCUGAGAGCCAGGUUACUUUCUUCACUAUCACUCCGACGCUUGUGUUGAUUCCCAAAUCUCAGUCUGCCCAGGGUCAUUCUCUUUCUGAAUUGCUCUUUCAGGAUUUAAUUUGAAUCCUGCAAAGUCCUGUUCAAGGCCCCCUUUUCCAUGAAGCCCUUCUUCCUUGUUGCAGCUCACAAAUAAGUGUGCCCUUUCUCAAAACACGUAUGAAACACCUCCUGCUUGUAUACCUUUAGCAGUAGUUCCUCAUAUUGCCUGGCAUUUAAACAUUUUUGUAUGCGUACAUCUUGCUUUCCUACUUAAAGCAAGAGCAGGACCACAUCUUUUUGUAUGCUCUGGCACAUGACUGUUGGACCACUUUGAUAUUGCUGAAUUAUAUAGACUCCUUUUAAAAUAAUUUGAAAUAUAAUUUUGGAGUAUAGACAUCUUGUCCAGUGCACUAGACAGGUGACCUUUGGCUUUGUUCAUUAAGCAUUUAGUGUCUUAGAAGUGAUAUGUUUACUGCAGAAAAAUUUGGAUAGCAUGCAAAAAAUGAAACAUACUAUCACAAUCCUAUGAUAUAACUUAAAAAUUUCUUUAUAGCUUCAUGGAGGUAUUUGAUGAAAAUUGUAUAUAUUUAAGGUAUAUAAUGUUUUGAUACAUGUAUACAUUGUGAAAUGAUUACCACAAGGAGGUUACUAAACAUCUCCAUCACCUUGUUAAAUUGAGUUAAACAAAUUUACAAGUUGACAAAUUACAUUUACAAAUUUAUGUAAUUUUUUACGCUUUUUUUUUUUCUCCUUUUUCUGGAGAACGGGGUCUCGCUAUACUGCCCAGGCAGGUCUCGAACUCCUGGGCUCAAGCUAUCCUCCCGCCUCUUGCCUCCCUAAGAGCUGGGAUUAUAGGCGUGAGCCACCCCACCCGGCCUAUGUCAUUUUUUUAUGUGGUGAGAAUAAAUAAUCUCAGCAAAUUUCAAGUAUACAAUUCAUUAUUACUAAGAUAGCCACCACACUGUAUGUCAGGGCUCCAGAACUUACUCAUCUCAUAGGAGGCAGCUACUUUUAACAUUCUUGGUGUAUAUCCAUCCUUCAGGAUUUUCUGUAUAUUUCUCUAACAGCAAAAGUUUUUGUUAGCUACAUCAUGUGAAAUGCCUGGGUAGACAAAUUUAAAGAUGUUAUUUGGGAUGGUGUGACUUGCACAAGCCACACAGCCUGCAUGGUGUCCACUUUGAGGGGGAUGCCCAUAGCUAUACUUAGAAGUCAUCCUCUAGAGCAAGCUUGUCCAAUUUGUUGUCCAUGGGCCACAUGCUGCCCAGGAUGGCUUUGAAGGUGGCCCAAAACAAAUUCAUAAACUUUUGUAAAACGUGAGAUUUUUUGUGAUUUUUUUUUUUUCGAGACACAGUCUCGUUCUGUCGCCCAGGCUGGAGUGCAAGUGGCGCGAUCUCCGCUCAUUGCAAGCUCCGCCUCUCGGGUUCAAGCAAUUCUCCUGCCUCAGCCACCCGAGUAGUUGGGAUUACAGGCACCCGCCAUCACGCCCGGCUAAUUUUUGUAUUUCUUUUAGUAGAGACCGGGUUUCAUCAUGUUGGCCAGGUUGGUCUUGAACUCCUGACUUCAGGUAAUCCGCCCUCCUUGGUCUCCCAAAGUGCUGGGAUACAGGCAUGAGCCACUGCACCCAGCUGUGACUUUUUUUUUUUUAAGCUCAUCAGCUAUUGUAUUAGUGUAUUUUAUGUGUAGCUCAAGACAAUUCUUCCAGUGUGGACCAGGAAAGCCAAAAGAUUGGACACCCCUGCCCUAGAGCAUCUGACGCCUGGAUACAAAAGAGCCUGUGGCUAUGACUAUCAGGAUUCUGGCCAUGAGGAAUUCCAUGACAUGGAGGGAAAAUGGCAACUUCAAAUUUGCACCCCCAGGUAUCAUGUGGGCAGGUGCUCCAUGUGGCUGGUGAUAGUUGUGAGUGAGCCUUGCACGGGCUUUCCCCCUAUCGGCUGUUCCAGAGCGAGAGGCUGCAGGUGUCCACUUACGUACCUGUGGCUAAGAUGCGCCUGAGCAAGUGAGGGCCAGUUAGUAUACAUAAUUUUUACAAAAUUUGGAUCAUAUUACAUAAAUAUCUUGCUUCAUGCACUUAAUAUGAAAUUUUGCCCAUGAUUUAUUUUUUACCUUAUUUUUAAGGGCCACCUAGUUAGAAUUUGAUUAUUUGAGCAACUAUUUAGUGCCUGUGAUGUGCCAGCCACUGCUAGGUUCUGGGGCUCAAAACACUGUGACAGAUGCUGUGAUACCACAACGUGGCCACAUUUUGUUUUCAAGACCUUGGCCAACCUUUGGUCUUCACAGCCACUGCCCUGGUAGUAAGGGACUUAGUUAAGUUUGGUGACUGCUUGAAGUCUAAGAUCACCAAAGUGGCUAAUGCAGGCACUGUGACAAUCUGGGCACUAGGAAAAGCAAUGUGGGCAGAAAUUCCUUGUUCGAGAGCCUUCUGGUUAUACUUUAAAAAGAAGGGAGCCUAGCAUCUUGUCAAAUCUUUGAGCCCACUCACUCAGAGGGCCUGUCACUCAUCCAGAAUUGAAUCUGCUGGUUUAACAGGUCAGGCAGUGUGAUUUGACAGCGUGAAUCUUAGAGUCCAGCCUUUGAACCUGGCGCUGAAUCCUGACUUUACUGCUUAUUCAGGGGGCCACUAGCUAAGUUAAUUUGUGAGCCUGGGCAACAUGGCGUGACCCAUCUCUACAAAAGAUACAAAAAUUAACUGGAUGUGGUGGUGCAUGCCUGUAGUUCAUAGCUACUCUGGAGGCUGAGGCGGGAGGAUAACCUGAGUGCGGGAGGUUGAGGUUGCAGUGAGCUGAAGUUGCACCACUGCACUCCAGCCUAGGUGACAGAGUGAGACCUUAUCUUAAUCUAAAAAAUAAAAUUUCUGAGCCUUAUUUUCCUCAUCUGUAAAAUGAAGAGAAUACCUAGCUCAUGGAGUUAGGAACAAGUAUGUUAAAUAUUUAUCAGAGUGUGCCUGACAGUGAGUUGAAAAUAUCUACUCUCUUUGGAUGAAAAAUAUUUAACACUUCACUCUCAGAUAUAAUUAUUAGCUGACUUUUUAGAUUCUUUUUUCUUUUACAUGAUGUAGUUCUCAGAUAUAUACGGGAUUUCUAGUUCUUAAAUGCCAGUAUUUUUUUUCUGUUAAAAUAUUUAUGAACUAUUUCAAACAUUCAGAAAAACUCAGGAUCAUACCCAUAAACCCACUGUUUAGAUUUUAAAAAGUUCAAUGUUUUUCUGUAUUUUAUCUCUUCAUUUUAAAAUAAAGUUUUGCACAUG